AUCGUUGCCCGACCGCUUUCCGGGAGACUGGAGUCGAAGGCCGUGAGGUAUUUUUCUAAGCCAGUGUUUUAGAAGGAGUAUGUGGAAGGGCAAGGAGUACCUAUAGAACCCCGGAGGAGGGUGAGGAGCAGAGCUGGUCAGCCAUAAUGGCAGGUGAAGAAAUUAAUGAAGACUAUCCAGUAGAAAUUCACGAGUAUUUGUCAGCGUUUGAGAAUUCCAUUGGUGCUGUGGAUGAGAUGCUGAAGACCAUGAUGUCUGUUUCUAGAAAUGAGUUGUUGCAGAAGUUGGAUCCACUUGAACAAGCAAAAGUGGAUUUGGUUUCUGCAUACACAUUAAAUUCAAUGUUUUGGGUUUAUUUGGCAACCCAAGGAGUUAAUCCUAAGGAACAUCCAGUAAAACAGGAAUUGGAAAGAAUCAGAGUAUAUAUGAACAGAGUCAAGGAAAUAACAGACAAGAAAAAGGCUGGCAAGCUGGACAGAGGUGCAGCUUCAAGAUUUGUAAAAAAUGCCCUCUGGGAACCAAAAUCGAAAAAUGCAUCAAAAGUUGCCAAUAAAGGAAAAAGUAAAAGUUAACUUUUUGGUUUUGAUGUACACAUAUUCAAAAAGUACAUCUUCCCCCCCCCCCCCCCCCCCGCAAAAUAAUUCUGUGGCAGGGCAAGGUUUAAAUGUGUUUCUUAUUAAUAUGUAAAUUCACAGUAAAUAUGUAAAGCUAAAUACUUUCCUCUCCAAAGAUCAUUAUCUUUAUUGAUUAGCACUGAGGAUUUUAACAUUGUGAUAUAUUAUAUAUUUAUAAUUUACCAUCUCUUGAUGAGACUCUUAUUUCUUUAUAUAGGUCAGUCUUGCAAGUACCAUUUUAUAAGCAGCUGUGAAAUUUAAGUGAAAUGUUCUUUGUAAACAUUUGUACUAUUUUAAAUGAAUAAUGACCUUAUGAAGUAUGCUAUCUGUAGGCUGAAAUUAUAGGUACAUCUGUUUUCACUAUAUGAUAUUAAGAAAGCGUGAAAUGACUUAAAUGUUCAUUUUUUUCUGUAUAGAUACUUUAUCAUGUUUUCAUGAUUUUAGGAAUUACUGCUUUGUUGAUAUUCAAAGUGUGAAACUAAAACUUUAUGGUUGUACUUUAAUUCUUGGCAUGUUGCCUCUAUGUCCCAUUUAAAAUAAAAUACAUUCUCAUUAACUUUAGAUGGGAAAUAAGGUUGUAUGUUGAUGGAUGAAUUUUGGCAUGAUGACUGUACUCUCAAUAAAGGCUGAAAAUGUUGUAUAACUGACCUGUGUAUUUUUAUCUUUUGAGUAAAUUUGCCUUCCAAAUUAGGAAGAUAGGUUUUAGAAGUCAUCACAAAUAGAGAAAUUCUUGAGUUUUUGUUCCUGAUGCAUGGUGUCCACAGUUCUUUUCAUCUCAUUUUUUUUCAGAUUUUUUUUAUUUCAUGUUUUUGAGGCUGUAUCAAGUACAUACAAGUGUUUUGGAACAACUUCUUAAGUUACCUAAUGCCACUUAAGCAGAUGAGAAGUCCAAAGGAGAUUACACUGUGUUUGUAUUGUGGUUUAUUUUUCUGGAAUAUUAGUUACAGAGAGUACUACAUAGUAAACCUUUUUUUAAAUGUCUAAGCCCAUGAAUUUUAAUUAUAUGCCCUUAAUGCUUUCAGUGUUUGAAUCCAUAUCAUUAUGUGUAGGAAUGCCAAGUAUAGUAAAGUACUUUAAUUUUUGAAAAAGGAGUUGUUAAAAUUUUCUGUGUGAUUAAUUCUCCAUAAGUAACCUUGAAUAAAUGGAUUUCUUGAUUUAUGAUAGCAGAUAUUGGAAAUGGUCUUAAAAUGUAAUGGAUUUUGUAAAGCAUGUUGAACUCUUUCUAUGACACAUGAAGAGGAAGUCACUGAUAGACGCAGAAGGUCUUUUCUGUCUCUGAUGUCAGUUUUUGAAGUGGAAGAACAUUAGUGAACAUUUAUAGUUAUUUUACUCCUUUUUUUGCCUUUGUCUCCAAAUUUCUAGCUAUUUUUAAAAAUAACCUCUUCAUGAGAGAAAUGUGUUACUGUUAAGAUCAAGUGUAGUGUACCUGUCUUUGUGUUAUUUAUUGCAAAGAAAUUUAUUUGGAUUUCUGUAUAUUUUCUAAUUUCAUAAAAGAAAAACAGCUUAAAUGAAAAAUGUUAUACAAUUGCAGAAAAUCAUUAUUGGUUUUAGCUAAGUUAUUGGUUUAUGAAAGUGCACCUCUACGUUCUGUUAAAUUGUGUAACUUUUAAGUGAGUAAUUCUUUCAUUAUUAGGUAGAAAUAAAAGUUUGAGUAUAUUCCAUUUUAUUAUGUAUAAUUUUAAAUACUUAGCACGUAAUAAGGAGCUGAAUGGCUGUA